AGACAAGAAGGAUGGUGCUGUGGCCGAGAUCUGUAGAUGCACACGGCUGGUAACAGAGCAACCGGGACCAAGGGACAACAAGAGCUCAGGAGAAGGGGAGAGACAGGUCGCCCAGAGAGUAGACAAUCCAGGGCUUGAGGAGGCUGGCUGUGCGGUUUAUUUUUUCUCUCCACAAAGACACACACUGUCUAAACUGUGUGGCUGGUUGUUACUAAGAAGCUGCUGCGAGAGGGAAAAAUGUAUUUAAUAAAAGGCCCUGUGUUUGUGGUCUUCUUGGGCUUGCUGUGAGCUCUGGAAAUCUUGAGGUGUGACCAGAUUUCAGCCUUCAAAACCAAGAUGGACUGCCCUUGAGAAGGGGUGGUCAGAGGGAAACAUGUUCACGCUCUCCCUCCUGAGCCGGGGCCACGGGAAGCUGGGCCAGGACAAACAGAAGUUAGAAGUCUACUUUGAACCAGAGGAUUACUUGAACUGGAGGUCCCCAGAAGACUAUGUUCCUGUCAGCAAACCUCAAGAUAAGAACAAUGCCAGUCAGCACUCCUGGAGCCUCUUUCUCCCUAAAACUUUCAGUACUAGAAAGGGUGCCCUGAUCCUGUACUCAGAAGGUUUUGCCAUUUCGGCAUGGACACCCAAAGAGAGGAGAAAAGGCCCCUACUGCCCCAGAGGUCCCUGGAGGAAGCUGGAUCUUGAACUGCACACACUUCAAGACCUCAAAGAAGCCAUCCUGGCAUAUGGAAGGCAGCAGGGAGAGCAGGACAGAGCCUGGCAACCAUACCUCCACUUCCGAAGCCAGCUGGAGAGCCAGGCCCAACGGCAGAUCCAGCCAGGGCAUUCAGCCAAGAGAUACCUCCGAGGCCUCCUGCGGACUUGGCCCCCAGACGCCAUGUAUAGGCUCUGGUGCGCAGGAUACAUCAAGGAUUCUGUGCUACUCCAGGACAGUCAACUUAAUGUACCAAAGAAGCUCAGGCCACAACAAGAUCUUUCAGGUGUACCCCCAAAAUACCAUCUCCUGCCUGUCUUCCCUUCAUUUUGGAUUCAACAAGGAAAAUCUUUUGAACAACGUCAACAGGGCCUGGAUGAAGGGGAAGCUGGAGCUGCUGGACACGUGGACCAGGGCCCUCUAGCCAAGAACCAUGGCAGUCAGGGGACUCGCUUGCCACCACGCAGGAAGCAGCCCUGGCAGGAAGAUGAAACGCAGGCAGAGGACACGUCAAUAGAGAAUCACCUUUGUUUAUAUGCUUCAAAGGAGAGCUACAAUGAAAAGACACAGCAAACCUCCAGGAAGGCCUUUGGGCAUGGCCGCAUCGAUCACUCUUGGCUCCCAAGUGACAAAUCCCACAUUACAUUCUGUGGAGGCGCCUUCCCUAAUAGGAAGGCAGAUCUCAGCGAUAAACAAAGGAACGUGAAACUCCACAAGGCCAGAAGCAGCCACUUGUUACAGGUGCUUCCUGCUGAAAGAAGCCUCUUCCCUCCUGUAGCAUCUGCCACUGGCUCCAGAAUAAUCACCCCUGGGGAAGUGAAGAAGAAAAAGGCACCAAAGGCUUUGAAAUUACCUCCUAUCUCAGAAGAACCACCCAGAGUCUUGGAGCCCCUGAAGAGCCAAUUUAAAGCCAAUGAGCCCCCAACAGAGCUCUUCAUCUUACCGGUGGAGAUUCAUUACCACACCAAACAACCCCCAAAAGAGAAAGCCCACAGAAGAGGUGCUCCACACCCUGAGUCAGAACCAGAAAGCAGCGAAGAAUCCACACCUGUGUGGAGACCUCCCCUGAAGCAUGCGUCCUUAGAAACACCAUGGGAGUUAACAGUGCAUCUCCCAGUGGACGCGAGCAGGGACACACUCUCACCUCAAGAUGAUGAUGCCCCACCUCACGAUGUGGCCCCACCAUUGGAUCUUCUACCCCCGAUUAAAGGAAAAAAAAGUCCUGAGAGCCAGAAGGGCGUGGACAGCCCUAGGACAUCAGACCACAACAGCCCCCCAAGUCUCCCGAACAUGAGAGUGCCCAGGAGGGCACUGCCAGCAGCUCAAGAAGAUUCCAGCGACCCUACACUGGGACACUUCUUGCUGGGUCCAGAUGGAGAAAAAGUCUGCCUGUCCCUCCCAGGGCAUACCCAAACCGAGGCGCUUCCAUCGGGUAAAGCCUAUGAAUCUGUCAAUUCAAAUAUCAGCCAUGAAGAGGAAGGGCCUAGUAGUCAGCAUUUCCUAAAAGCAAACACUGAACCUAGAGCCAAUCUUCACAUGAACCUUUAUGAAACCUCACCGUUGACCCAAACAACAGAGAAGCAGGGAGCCCAGCAGUCCUUGGAGGCAGCAGCUCAGAAGACAGGAGAGCCUCAAAGUUGUAUAAAUAAAGCGCUGAUAUGUUCAAACAGAAAAGAAUUUUACACGCGCAAGCUGCACAUCGACAUGACGCCGUUCCUGAAGGAAAGUGGAAAUGCACUGGACUAUCAGGAAGAAGCAGGGAGACCCCUCAGAGAAACUCACCACAACGACCAAGACCCAGAGCCAAGGAGUAUGACCCUUGACUCUCCCAGGGCUUCCCGGACUGAGCACAUCCAGACCCCAGAAGCAGAUAUUGUGCAAAAAGUGGGCAGAGAUUAUGAUGUACACCACCUACACAGAGGACUUCUGGGAUACGGGCCUGAGUCACCCGAGAGGUUGAGUGCUGUGUAUACAUCUCUUCUUCCAAGAGAAAGAGAAGGGAAGGCUGAACCAAGACUGUUUAGCCAGGAGACAUCAGCCAACAUCAGUCAUGAGAGGGAUUUGAUUAACGAGGCCAAGAGAAAGGAAAAACCCAAGAAAGACAAAACCAAAGGACCCAAAAGCGAGAGAGAAGGAAAGGUCUACGGGCAAGCAGAGGCUGCCAUUGGAAAGUCAAAGGACUCAAAGGCUAAAAAAAAAUUAGAAAAAAAAACAAGACCCCAAAGGAAAAGGACACAGAAGGAAAGAAAUCUGGAGAUAGCGGCAGAGCUGAGCGGGCCUGAUGUCAGCUAUGAGGAAACAGAAGACACCUCAAAUAGAGGUUCCUUUGCCUCAGACUCCUUUGUAGAGGACCCUUGGCUUUCUCCCAAAUAUGAUGCCCAGGAAAGCCAAGUUUCUCUAGAUGGAAGAUCAUCACCCUCUCAGAUUGCAACUGUCACUGGCAACAUGGAAUCUAAAGAAGAGAGAAGAUGUGAGGACCCUUCCAAGGCCCUCCUCACUAAGAGGGAGCAGGAGAAGGCUUCCUGGGACAGGCUUCGAGCAGAAAGAGCCGAGAUGAGGUGGCUGGAGGUGGAGAAGAAGAGAAGGGAGCAGGAAGAGCAAAGGCAGCUCCAGCAGGAGCAGCUGGAGAGAGCAAAAAAGAUGGAGGAGGAGCUGGAGCUGGAGCAGCAGAGACGUACAGAAGAGAUCCGCUUGAGGAAACAGAGACUCCAAGAAGAACAGCAGCGGCAGGAGGAGGAGGAGAGAAAGCAGCAGCUCCGGUUGAAAGCAGCCCAGGAGAGAGCCCGGCAACAGCAAGAGGAGUUUCGGAGGAAACUGCGAGAACUACAGAGAAAAAAGCAGCAGGAGGAAGCCGAGAGGGCCGAGGCAGAGAAGCAAAGGCAAGAGGAAUUGGAAAUGCAGUUAGAAGAAGAACAAAAACACCUGAUGGAAAUGGCUGAAGAGGAACGACUGGAGUACCAGCGGCGGAAACAGGAAGCAGAAGAGAAGGCUCGGCUGGAGGCAGAGGAGAGGAGGCAAAAAGAAGAGGAAGCAGCAAGACUGGCUCUGGAAGAAGCCACGAAACAAGCCCAGGAACAAGCCAGGCAAAAAGCUGCUUUGGAGAAACAUUUUCAUUUCUAUCAAGAACUCCAUAAGGAAGCCAGUGGCCUGCAGUGGACACAGAACAUUUCCAGACCAUGGGUUUACUCUUAUUUCCAGUUCCUACAAAUACCCAGGCCUUAAGGCUAGAAGAAAACUAAAAAAUUUAGGAUGUUGCAGUCAAGCACCAGAUAAGAGUGACUUCCCUAAAUGUUAUUCAAGGUCCCUUCAGAAAUCUGAUAAUCUGUUAAAAUUUUUGUUGUGAAAUGCCUAUUUUAUCAGCACUGCUAACCAGAUAAGCACACAUUUAAGUUAACCAUAUCAGAGUGCAAUGCAUUUCGAAAAAUCCAAAAAA